AGAGACCUCCUGGGGAGCCGCCGCCGCCGCCCUCUCGGCCAUCGCUGCCUCCGCCGCCUGCUCCACCUCGAGGGACGCGAGCGGGCGGCGGGGCUGGCCGUGAGAGAGACAGGAGAGGAAGGAGGGCAGGGGCGGAGUUGCCCGCCUUAGCCCCCGCCCCCGGCCGCGGCCCCGGGCCCUGCCCCGCGCGGCCCUGCCCGGCCCACCGAGCCCUGGUGUGGCAGCGGCUCAUGGCGGCCGUGGGGCCCCCGCAGCAGCAGGUGCGGAUGGCCCAUCAGCAGGUCUGGGCGGCGCUCGAAGUGGCGCUCCGGGUGCCCUGCCUUUACAUCAUCGACGCCAUCUUCAACUCCUACCCGGAUUCCAGCCAAAGCCGGUUCUGCAUCGUGCUCCAGAUCUUCCUCCGGCUCUUUGAUGACUUGACAUUUUGGCACAGAAUACAUUUUAAAUCCCUGGACAGAGUCAUCACUUAAAUGAACUAGCCCUUGCUUAUAUGUGCAGUGGAUUGUGAAAUGCGUCUACUGUAAUAAUAUGCAAUGUCUUGAUUACCUGCUGAAAUAAGGUGUAUUUGCAUCCAGUAUUGUUCUGAUCUUGUCACAACGAUCACUUUUCAAGUUUUACACGUACAGCUCAGCCUUUCUGUUAGCUGCAACUUCAGUGUUGGUGAAUUAUUAUGCUUCUUUGCACAUUGACUUCUAUGGUGCCUACAACACGUCAGCUUUUGGAAUUGAGCUGCUUCCUCGAAAAGGUCCCUCGCUGUGGAUGGCACUUAUCGUUCUACAGCUAACAUUUGGAAUUGGAUACGUUACACUACUCCAGAUUCAUUCCAUCUAUUCACAAUUAAUUAUUUUGGAUCUCUUGGUUCCUGUAAUAGGCUUAAUCACAGAGCUACCAUUACACAUCAGAGAGACUUUACUGUUUACUUCUUCCUUGAUUCUCACAUUAAAUACAGUGUUUGUCCUGGCAGUGAAACUGAAGUGGUUUUAUUAUUCCACACGAUAUGUUUAUCUUUUGGUGAGGCACAUGUAUCGAAUUUACGGAUUACAGUUAUUGAUGGAGGACACAUGGAAGAGGAUUCGUUUCCCAGACAUACUACGAGUCUUUUGGCUAACAAGAGUUACAGCUCAGGCUACAGUGUUAAUGUACAUCUUAAGGAUGGCAAAUGAAACUGAUUCCUUCUUUAUUUCUUGGGAUGAUUUUUGGGACCUCAUUUGCAAUCUUAUAAUUAGUGGGUGCGAUUCUACACUAACUGUACUGGGCAUGAGUGCUGUAAUUUCCUCAGUAGCCCAUUAUUUGGGGCUUGGAAUAUUGGCCUUUAUUGGAUCAACUGAGGAAGAUGACAGGCGUCUUGGCUUUGUUGCACCUGUUUUAUUUUUUAUUUUGGCUCUUCAGACUGGGUUAAGUGGGCUAAGACCAGAAGAGAGACUUAUUCGCUUAAGUAGAAACAUGUGCCUUUUAUUAACUGCAGUCCUGCAUUUUAUCCAUGGAAUGACAGACCCUGUAUUAAUGUCUCUCAGUGCCUCUCAUGUGUCAUCUUUUCGUAGACAUUUUCCUGUGCUGUUUGUCUCUGCUUGCCUGUUUAUUCUUCCUGUCUUACUCAGUUAUGUUCUUUGGCAUCACUAUGCACUAAAUACAUGGUUGUUUGCAGUUACAGCAUUUUGUGUGGAACUGUGCUUAAAAGUAAUUGUUUCUCUCACUGUUUAUACGUUAUUCAUGAUUGAUGGCUACUAUAAUGUCCUCUGGGAAAAGCUUGACGAUUAUGUCUACUACGUUCGUUCAACAGGCAGUAUUAUUGAAUUUAUAUUUGGAGUUGUAAUGUUUGGAAAUGGGGCUUACACUAUGAUGUUUGAGUCGGGAAGUAAAAUUCGGGCUUUUAUGAUGUGCCUACAUGCAUAUUUUAACAUCUACUUACAAGCCAAAAAUGGCUGGAAGACAUUUAUGAAUCGUAGGACUGCUGUGAAGAAAAUUAAUUCACUUCCUGAAAUAAAAGGGAGCCGCUUACAAGAAAUAAAUGAUGUAUGUGCAAUCUGCUAUCAUGAGUUUACAACAUCUGCUCGUAUUACACCGUGUAAUCAUUAUUUCCAUGCACUUUGCCUUCGGAAAUGGCUGUACAUUCAAGAUACUUGUCCAAUGUGCCAUCAGAAAGUAUACAUCGAAGAUGAUAUCAAGGAUAAUUCAAAUGUAUCUAACAACAAUGGAUUUAUUCCACCCAAUGAAACUCCAGAGGAAGCUGUAAGAGAAGCUGCUGCUGAAUCUGACAGGGAAUUGAACGAAGAUGACAGUACAGAUUGUGAUGAUGAUGUUCAAAGAGAAAGAAAUGGAGUGAUUCAGCACACAGGCGCAGCAGCUGAAGAAUUUAAUGAUGAUACUGACUGAUGAAAAUAGCAUUUAUUAAUGAUUGAGGUAUUUGUUUAAAAUUCAGUUCAUCCAAAAUGGAGUAAUAUCCUUCACCUUCAGUGUGUAACCAAGCACAAAAACAGUAUCAAUGUUGAAUCUGUGAAUGGUUUUCCGUUUACUGUGAUGUGCUACUGUAAAUAUACCUCUUUAAUUACUUCUGGUCUCUUUGGUGACCUGUUUAAAUUUGUGUACAUUAUUGUACAUAGAAUAAAAUGUUUUCACAUUUUUAUGACAAAAUUUGAACAAAUAGCUUUUUAAUAGAUGUAAUGAUCAUAUGGUGCGUCACCUGUGCCAAAUAUUCUUCAAUGAAAUUAUAUAAUGUAACUUUGGACCUCAGUUUUUCUUUAGAAAUGGGUGGGAGAAUGAAAAUGCAAAUCAGGAAACCACAUUAAAGUCAAGGAAAUAAAAUAAUUUGACCAGAGGAUAAAGGACAUGAGAGAGUAUUUUAAAACUAAAGAAAAAAUUAGCUGCCAGAAGCAACUGAGGACCUUUUUUGAAACUUGAGUAGCAGUGUAAUUGAGCUGAGUUUGAAAGUCCUGAUUCAGAGAGAGACUGAGGGUUGACAAAUAAACUGUAUCAACUAAACUUUGAUAUAAACCAGAAUGUGCUAAAUGUUUUUUAUGUAAAAUUGUAUAUUUGUUAGCCAUUCUGUGUCUGCAGUAUUGUCAUAAAAUUGUCCUUUCAUUCUUUUGAAGAUAUUACAAAACAAAAAUAGUUUUUUUUAAAUUGUUUUAAACUAAGAUACUCAAUGAUAUAAAAACAUCCUGAUCUGAUUUUACGAGAAAAAGAAGGGGAAUGGUGGGGAAUGGUGUGUACCGAUAUAUAGUAUUUCUUUAGACAACUUGCAGAUAAUUUCUUUAUUGAAACUAUCAGGAAGUUUUACUAUGAAAUUUUACAUACAUGAUGGAAAGUGGAAGACAUAUACCAAUUAUAUUCCAGGAAAAAAUACUUUA